AGUCCUGGACGGCGCCGGGCCGCCCAAGCGCGCCGAGGAGAGGGGGCGGCAAACUUCGGGCCGAGCGGCGCCGGGGCCCGCGCGCGGAGUCUCCCUCCGGGCACCACGGGGGCCGCCGUCCUGGCACCAACUUGAGGGGCUGUGCGGCGGAGGGCGGCUGCGGAGCGCCCGCGCGGGCUGCACCUGCUCAGGGAGCUGCCCCUCUGUUGUUGUUGUUAUUUUCCUUCUUGGCGUGCCAUCGAGGCUUUUGGGGGAAAAAAAGACUGCCUGCAAGGGAUGGUCAUACUCCUGGCUGCACUUCCAGAGUCUUGAAGAAGAAAGCAGAUGUGGAUACCUAAAUAUAGGGAAGAAAUACUUGUGUUGGCUGCAUUUCCAGGGAUGCUACCAGAGCUCAAGGCUGUCACCUGGUCUUGCCCAGAAGAGCCGUUCUUAGAGGCAGGACUUGAUGAAGGCUUUCCUGCUGAUGGAAUAGGUUUGCUAGAGCUGGCCUUGGAAUUAGAACCCUUCAUGUGGCCUUUAUAAAUAUGCGUUUGAGACAGAGUUAUAUGCAGAAGUUGAAAAUGCCUGGAAGAUUUCUGGUUUCUUUCACUACUUAUCCUGCCUUUUUGCAUCGCUGCCAGAUUUGGAUGAUAUGAUAUUCAGAGGGGCACCUUAAUCAAAGCCAUUCUUCAACAAGACCCACCUGGCAUAAGAUUGCACACAUAAUUCAAGAUGGCCAGUCAACCUCCUGAAGACACUGCGGAGUCUCAGGCCUCUGAUGAGCUGGAGUGCAAAAUCUGUUACAAUCGAUACAAUCUGAAACAGAGGAAACCCAAAGUGCUGGAGUGUUGUCAUAGGGUUUGUGCCAAAUGCCUCUACAAGAUCAUAGACUUUGGGGACUCCCCACAAGGUGUCAUUGUCUGUCCUUUCUGCAGGUUUGAGACGUGCCUGCCAGAUGAUGAAGUUAGUAGCCUGCCCGAUGACAACAACAUCCUUGUAAACUUGACUUGUGGAGGCAAAGGGAAGAAGUGCCUGCCAGAGAACCCUACUGAGCUGCUGCUCACCCCCAAGAGGCUGGCCUCUCUGGUCAGUCCUUCUCACACGUCCUCCAACUGCCUGGUCAUAACCAUCAUGGAGGUGCAGAGAGAGAGCUCCCCGUCCCUGAGCUCCACUCCUGUGGUAGAAUUUUAUAGGCCUGCGAGUUUCGACUCUGUCACCACUGUGUCACACAACUGGACUGUGUGGAACUGCACGUCCCUGCUGUUUCAGACAUCCAUCCGGGUGUUAGUGUGGUUGCUAGGUUUGCUCUACUUCAGCUCCUUACCCUUAGGAAUCUACUUACUGGUGUCUAAGAAAGUCACCCUUGGGGUCGUCUUUGUCAGCCUGGUCCCUUCGAGCCUCGUUAUUCUUAUGGUGUAUGGUUUUUGCCAGUGUGUUUGUCAUGAAUUUCUAGACUGUAUGGCACCUCCUUCUUAACUGAUAUGCAAAAUAAGAAAUUGGACACACAUUGCCCUGUUUGAGUGUGAAGUUAGAUAAUUUAUAAUUUAUUUUCUUUUAUGUUCUUUAUGAUUAGUAUCCAUGACAUUAACAAAACCCUUGGCCACAUGUUGACUUGAUUGGUUUUCCUGUAGGCUGGAAGUAAAAAUGUUCAUUUCUACUUAGGGGUUAGCAAAAUUGUAUAAGCUCACACUUCAUGGAGCACUGACAGCAGUGAGUCUUCCCAGAGAAAGGACAGGGUUUCUCUCAGCACUGCCAGACAGACGGCAGGGGUGUGGUGUGUUAUACUAUAGGGAGAGCAUGGAUCCCUCCUUUCGUAUUCAUGGAUGUUCUAUGAUGGCAGUUGGACACAAGAGGAAAGUUGCUCUGAGACACAAAGUGUGUACUCCUUUCCCACCCCAUACCCCUGGUAUUGGAACACCCUAGAAUUGUCUUCAGGUGUUUUCUCUCUUAAGUCACUCUCUGUGGUCGGCGAUCCCAUUGAGAUACUUGUUUCCUCUGCCCAUUCUCCCUUGCCAAGAGGAAACUCGGUUCCAUUCCCUUGGGUAGUUUCAACUGAAUACCAGUUUUGCCACAUUACUAAGGAGAAUGAAAAGCACUGAGGAAUUUGCAUCACAGUCAGCUUCAUGGCAGAAUGUGGCCAUUUGUCCUUGAGACACACUCUUUCCUCCAUGUCUGUUUUCCUCUCUCCUCAGUCUUAUCUGAGAAGAAUGGAGGAGAAGGAACUUCUCAUACAGCGGUUAUUAUUGAUGAAAACCUUCAUUUGAGUCUUUCCUUAUAACAUCUUAGUUUUGGUUUUUUUAAACCACAUUGCCCAAUCAGCCUCACCCCUUGUCCUGAAAAGGUUCCAUUUAAAUUAGUUGCUAUAAAUUCAUCAAUACUUUUUUUCCCUAUUAUAUUUUUGGUUCUAUUAGGAUUUACUUAACUGAAUCUUAUAACAAUUCGAGGUGAACUGUGGCAAUGAAAACCAGAAACAGUUAAUGAGAUGCUUCAGCUCACAGUUUGAAGUGCUGAGAACCUAAGUAUUUUGCUGUACGGUACUGAGCUGUACCAAAAUAUGAUGGUUUAGGUUUAUGUGCAAGACUUUGUGUUGUAGUCUAGACAAAGGGGUGGGCAAGAGACAUGCAAAGCUGAAGCCCUGCUUGAAAAGACCCUUCAAGGAAGUAAAAUGGCAGGGGCAGAGUGCAGCUUAACAUGUUGCUAUCCCUGUUGUUUUUGAGUUGGUUUUGGAAUGGAUUCAAGUUCUUACACAAUUUAUUUUGAAUACAAGCAUAAUCUAGGUGAUUUGAGUUAAUGAACUUCUUUUCAUGAUGUAGGGAAAGUUGAAUGUAUAUAUUUCUAAGAAGAAUUUGUUUAGCAGAUUACAAGUUGGCAAAAUAGACUGUUCACAGAAACUAGGCAAAAAUUUAAAAAAACAUUCUAGUCUCUAAAACCCAUUACUAAUGAUUAACAUUAAAAUAUUUGUAACUCUUAGAAAGGGGGCAUUACUAAGACGACUUUAACUUGUUAUGAAAUCUUUGUUGUGUGAUGCAGGUACAGUGCGCCCAUUCCAACUGGAAUAGCAGUUUGAUUUUAAUUGUAAAACUAAACUUCGGGAAUAUGUAUGCCCAAAGUAAGUAGGAUGAGAAUAGUAUACAUGGGAUAUGGUCCAAUGAAUUUAAGCCCCAAGAUACAGCUAAAUACAUUUAUGAUUUCAUAAAAUCUAGUUUAGAUAGCAUUGUGAUGCAAUUUCCAGAAAUCCAUUUGUGUUUAGAGUAAAUACCAUGUUUAGAAGAUGUUUUGUGGUUUGGAUUUAUAUAUUUGUAAGGUUUUUUUAAAAAAAUGUUCGUUUUGUUUGAAAUGUAACAUUGAGUAAAUUGGUGAGUUAUAUAAUGAGAUUUCUAGAAAGCUCUGGACAUGGGUACGAUGUGUUUUGCUUCUCUGUAUAAUGUCUACAGUGAUAAACUUGUGUCUCCGUGUAUUGUGGCAGUCUUUUUUUCUAGUUAAUUUGGCUUUAGAGAGCAAUCUUUGUAUGACACCAGAAAACUCUUCAUGCUAUUGAAUGAUAAAAAGAUAAUGCUUUAAUAUUUUAUUCACUGUGAUACUAUUUUGUUUGUCUAUUAAAUUGUUAUUAUUUCCAAAUUUAGAAGUUUGAUUUCUCUGACUUAUGGUUAAAAUUCAGUUAUGACUUUGCACCUCUGUUAGCUUUAGAUAACGGCAAACAUGAACAUUCAGAAACGUUGGUUCAGCUAAUGCCUUUAUCAUGCCCGUGAAGACUUCAGAACUUUCCAACAAAGGGGACCUAACCCAUCACACUUUUAAAAGGCCUUCAUAGUUUUUUUAUUUUAUUUUAUUUUAUUUUAUUUUAUUUUAUUUUAUUUAUUUAUUUUAAAGCAGGGGAGAAAAAUUAGGGGAGAUGAAAUAAAAAUAUCGUCUUUAUAAAUAAA